GUUAUGGGCAUUCCACAGGAACUUAAAACAGACAACGGGCCAGGCUACUGCACUAAAUCUUUAGAAACAUUCUUACAACAAUGGGGUGUUCGACAUAGUACUGGCAUACCCUAUAAUUCUCAAGCACAGGCCAUUGUUGAACUUGCAAACAGAACUUUAAAAACUCAAUUACAAAAACAAAAGGCAAAGAGGGGGGAAUACUCCACUCCCUAUAUGCAGCUACAACUGGCUCUUAUUAUUUUAAAUUUUUUGAACUUGUCCAGAGAUCAGUUUACAACUGCAGCAGAGCAGCAUCUAACAGGGCAAAAAAUAAAUCCCCAUGAAGGAAACCUUGUGUGGUGGAAAGAUGUCAGAACAAAGACCUGGGAAGAGGGGAGAAUCAUUACAUGGGGUAGAGGGUUUUCUUGUAUUUCACCAGGAGAAAAUCAGCUUCCUCUCUGGGUGCCUACAAGACAUCUUAAGCUGUGCCGUGAGUCAGAAUCCAAGGAAGAGGAGAAGACCUCGGAACUUUGCACUCCCAACUUGCCUGAUGGCUCAAAUGAAGAUUUCUGCUGAGCAGAAGGUGACCAGCAAGACUCACCAGUCAACUCCACCGACCUGGGGGCAGAUUAAGAGAUUGACCCAGCUUGCAGAAGAGGACCUGAAGUCUCAGGACAAACCGUGGACCUCCUGCAAUCUGCUGGUAGCUAUGAUGGUGGUAAUUACCCUGGCAGUGAGUCUCCCUGUAGCUGAGGCUGAUCAAAAUUAUACCUAUUGGGAUUACAUUCCAUUCCCUCCACUGAUUAGACCUCUUACUUGGCUGAACUCCCCAGUUGAGGUUUAUGUUAAUAAUAGUGUUUGGAUGCCCGGACCAACUGAUAACCAAGGCCCUACUCAUCCAGAGGAGGAAGGAAUCAAUUGGAGACUUGUUAUUUUACCGAGGCUGUGAGAGAAAUGGCAUAUUUUCAGAUAUGUCCAGAUUACUUUGAGGAAUUAAGGUUGACUUUUUAGACCCGAAAGGAAGCCUCUUGGAAAGACUGGCCUGGCACUUUUUCUAUGCAGUUGCUUUACAAGGUUCCUGACCUGUGGUCAGUAAAGAAUGUCACUUUAUGACAGGCCCAGAAAUCUCAAGUUAUUUUGGGACUUUGAGAAGAAACAACUUCACACAAUUCGUAUGGGUAUCACAGGCAAUCUGAUAAAUCCCUGACUUGAAUAGCUUUGAGAGGCCUUUCAAAUCAGAGAUUCCUUAUGAAAAGUUCAAACAAAGCCAAUCAAAAAAGCAAAACGUUAUUCUUGCUGCACUUUAUGCAAAUAAUUAGACCACAUUUAACCAGACUAAAAUCUACUUUGCACACAAAUUAGUUUUAUUAUAAUUUGUAUCUGGUACAAAAAGGGAUCCAGAGAGAGAGAGAGA